CUUGUGGACUGCGCCGGGCAUGCUCGGCGGUGUGACGGCUCAGGACUGCAUUUCCCAGAGGCUGCAGCUAUCCGGCCAAUGUAGCCUGAAACUACAUUUCUCAGCGGCCACUGGAACGACCUCAAUCUCUGCCUCCUCGCCAGUUCAUUGUGGUCGUUGACCCGGCAGCGAGCUUUGGAGUUCAUCGAGGGAGAAGUCAGCGCCCAGCUCCGAGGUUGGAGCAGCCCCGCCGGGCAACUUGAAUUUCUGCAAACGAACACAGCACCGGGAGCUCUGCAGACCUGUGUCGGCGCGGAACCCGGACUGAGACAUGCGUGAGCGUUGGGUGGACCGGGCGAGGAUCCCGGGCCGGCGAGUGCGGGAGCGGCAGGGCAGGGAGGGUGCGUCGGCCGGGGCCGGUGUGCAUCCGCGAAGACUGGGUGCAUGGCCUCCAUGCGAACCUGAGCUAUUAAUAUUUGUUACUAUUUUGGAUAAAAUCACUGUAAUUGAUUUAUGUAAAGGAGCAAAAGACUCUUCAACUCUCAGUUUAAAAAGGAAACGAUAGUUAUGAUACCUUUUGCAUGCAGCGGGAAGAAAUGGGAUUGCCAGGAAGCCUCUUCUUGUUUGGAAAAAACUGUAUAAAGUAUUUACACCUUUUAAAGAUGAGAGCAAUGUCAUCUGAAAAUUAUCAGUGCAGGGAAAAGGACUUCAAAGGAUCUGUUGUGCAGAUUACUUAACUAAUGACAAAAUUAUGUAAGAAAGGAGAGCAAGAUGACAGCUGUAAACAUUUCCAUCAAUCUCCAUAUUGCACAGAAAUAGGACCCAGCUUUUUCUUAAGCUUUUGAACUUCUCAGAUAGAGGAACCCCAGUGAAGACUGAUCAGUUCUUACAAUUCUCAAAGCAUGGCCCAUAAAUAUGUGGGUUUGCAGUAUCACGGAUCAGUGACAUUUGAGGAUGUGGCCAUAGCCUUCUCCCAGCAGGAGUGGGAGAGUCUGGACUCUUCCCAGAGGGGCUUGUACAGAGAUGUGAUGUUGGAGAACUACAGGAACUUGGUGUCAAUGGCAGGACAUUCCCGUUCUAAACCACAUGUGAUCGCCUUAUUGGAACAAUGGAAAGAGCCUGAAGUGACAGUGAGGAAAGAUGGAAGAAGAUGGUGCACAGAUUUGCAGUUGGAAGAUGAUACAAUCGGCUGUAAAGAAAUGCCCACCUCUGAAAACUGUCCAUCUUUUGCUCUACAUCAGAAAAUAAGUAGACAGAAACCACGUGAAUGUCAGGAAUAUGGAAAGACCCUUUGUCAAGACUCAAAGCCUGUUCAACAUGAAAGAAUACAUAGUAGUGAAAAACCCAACAGAUGUAAAGAAUGUGGGAAGAACUUUAGUAAUGGACAUCAACUCACCAUACAUCAGAGAUUGCAUGUUGGUGAGAAACCCUAUAAAUAUGAAAAAUGUGGGAAGGCCUUUAUCAGUGGCUCAGCCUUUGUUAAGCAUGGGAGAAUUCACACUGGUGAGAAGCCACUCAAAUGUAAGCAAUGUGGAAAGACUAUUAGUGGUAGCUAUCAACUUACAGUACAUAAGAGUAUUCAUACUGGGAAGAAACCAUAUGAGUGCGGGGAAUGUGGGAAAGCUUUUCUAGUAUAUGGAAAGCUUACCCGGCAUCAGAGUACUCACACUGGUGAAAAACCCUUUGGGUGUGAGGAGUGUGGGAAGGCCUUCAGUACCUUUUCAUACCUGGUUCAACAUCAGCGAAUUCAUACCAGUGAAAAACCUUACGAAUGCAAAGAAUGUGGGAAGGCCUUUAGCACUAGCUCACCCCUUGCUAAGCAUCAGAGAAUUCAUACUGGCGAGAAACCCUAUGAAUGUAAGGAGUGUGGGAAGUCCUUCACUGUGUAUGGACAGCUUACUCGACAUCAGAGUAUUCAUACUGGUGAGAAACCUUUUGAAUGUAAGGAAUGUGGAAAGGCCUUUAGACUUAGUUCCUUCCUUCAUGCACAUCAGCGAAUUCAUGCAGAGAUAAAGCCCUACGGAUGCAAGGAAUGCGGGAGAACCUUCAGUCGUGCCUCAUAUCUUGUUCAACAUGGAAGACUUCACACUGGCGAGAAGCCCUAUGAAUGUAAGGAGUGUGGCAAGGCCUUUAGUACUGGCUCAUACCUUGUUCAGCAUCAGAGGAUCCAUACUGGGGAGAAACCCUAUGAAUGUAAGGAAUGUGGCAAAGCCUUUAUUAGUCGCCAUCAGCUUACCGUACAUCAAAGGGUUCAUACUGGAGAGAAACCCUAUGAGUGUAAGGAAUGUGGCAAGGCCUUCAGAGUGCACGUACAUCUCACACAGCAUCGGAAAAUUCAUACUGAUGUAAAGCCCUAUGAAUGUAAGGAAUGUGGAAAGACUUUUAGUCGAGCCUCGUACCUUGUACAACAUAGCAGAAUCCAUACUGGUAAGAAGCCCUAUGAGUGUAAGGAGUGUGGCAAGGCCUUCAGUUCUGGCUCAUACCUUGUUCAGCAUCAAAGAAUUCAUACUGGGGAGAAACCCUAUGAAUGUAACAAAUGUGGGAAAGCCUUUACUGUUUAUGGACAACUUAUUGGACAUCAGAGUGUUCACACUGGUGAGAAACCUUUUGAAUGUAAGGAAUGCGGGAAGGCCUUUAGACUUAAUUCAUUCCUUACUGAACAUCAGCGGGUACACACUGGUGAGAAACCCUUUAAAUGCAAAAAAUGUGGGAAGACCUUUAGAUACAGUUCAGCCCUUAAAGUGCAUCUGAGAAAACAUAUGAGUGUUAUACCCUAAGAGUCUGAGGAGUGUGGGAAGUGCUUCGUGUGUGGCUCAAACAUUGUUGAACAUCGGGGAAUUUAUGCUGGUAGGAAACUUUCAAAUGUGAAGAAUAUUGGCAGGUCUAUUCUCAUCUUAUAAUUCAUAAUAUAACUCAGAAAACAUAAGAAUAUUCCUUUGUCAUUUAUAGGUUUGUAAUACCAAUAUUUAUACUGGUGGACCAUUCAGAAAAAGUGGGAAACGUUAUUACUUAAUGGUUACAGCACUGACAGCAUGAACUUUUAUAUGAUGCAUUUAUUCUAAUGUGAUUGUAUGAACAAGUGAAUAAAAAACCUUGGACCUCCUAAA